UGGACUUCCUCCAUCCAGGCAGUGCGUAGUAGCCCGGGCUCACAGUGUGGCCUUAAGCGAGUCACUGGCACUCCAAAGUGAAAGCCAUCCCUAGCAUUCCUGGAUUCACCAGAUUCCUGGAGAGCGGCCCCCUUGGACCUCAAACUACAUUUCCCAUGAGCCUCUGCAGUUCCUUGGCCAAUGCCCUGGACUCAGAACUACAUUUCCCAUGAGCCUCUGGGGCCUAAGCAACACCUCUGAGGCCAUUCUUCUCCUAGGAGCCCUCCUUAUGGACCUGGAGACCCCAGAGGAGAUGCAGGCUCGGAGCCUGGGCAGGCCCAUCAAAUCCUCAAAGCAGUACCUGCGGCAGGUCAUUGCAGAGUACGAGGCACUGGACCGAGAACUCCCGUGCAUCCGGAAGUUCCCCACACCACCAGCUUCCCAGCCCCUCUGCCUCUGCAUGGAGACCUUGCCCGAGGAGGAUUUUACCCACCUGGAGGUGCUGCAAGCCCUGGAGGCCCAGUUACCAGGGGCCAUGGAGAGCGGGCGCGUGAGCAGCAUCCGCUUUGAGAACAUGAACGUCAUCUGUGGGACUGCUGGGCGCCGGAACCGGUGGCUCAUCGCGGUCACGGACUUCCAGACGCGCUCGCGCUUGCUGCGCUCCGGGCUCAGUCCCCGCGGGCUUGCGCACCAGAUCGUGCGCCACGACGACCUCCUGCUGGGCGACUACCGCCUGCACCUGCGCCGCUCCCUGGUCCGGCGGCGCAUGCUCGAGGCCCUGGGGGCGGAGCCGAACGAGGAGGCCUGACGCCCGGGCGGGCCCCGGCAGCGCUUGCGCACCGCCCCGCGGGCUGGGGCCACCCACCCGGAGCCCCGGAGGACAGGGGGCGUUGCCUUCCCAGGAAGGAGGCGGGGCCGGCUCGAGGGGGUGGAUACUGUGAGUUUAAUUAUAAAGAAUGACCUGGUACAAAA